GAUCAAUCCCGAGGCUGCUGAGAGACGGUGGCGCGAUUGGGACAGUCGCCAGGGAUGGCUGAGCGUGAAGAUGCAGCGGGUGUCCGGGCUGCUCUCCUGGACGCUGAGCAGAGUCCUGUGGCUCUCCGGCCUCUCUGAGCCGGGAGCUGCCCGGCAGCCCCGGAUCAUGGAAGAGAAAGCGCUAGAAGUUUAUGAUUUGAUUAGAACUAUCCGGGACCCAGAAAAGCCCAAUACUUUAGAAGAACUGGAAGUGGUCUCGGAAAGUUGUGUGGAAGUUCAGGAGAUAAAUGAAGAAGAAUAUCUGGUUAUUAUCAGGUUCACGCCAACAGUACCUCAUUGCUCUUUGGCGACUCUUAUUGUUGGAAAUCUACAUUUCUGAAGGAACCCACUCAACAGAAGAAGACAGUAAGUGAAUGUUGAAACAUAAUUGAAAAACAACUUCAGAUAGUAUUUUAUCUUGGAUACUGGAUUCUUCUGCCAGCCAAGAAUCUACUGGGUUACUUUCAAAAAAGUGCACAAUUGGUUAUUGGCUCUUCCUUCCUAGGUGAGGAAACCUAGGCAUUUCAAAGAAGUAAUUUUUGCAGUGGACUCCGAGUGCACUAGAGCCCACGGAUGUUGACUGGUUUAGGCCAGUGGCUACACAUCUGUAAAGAAUAUCCAGUGCUGGGGACCUUGACUUAUGAGCUCUAAGUAGGCUUCUUUUCUUUGGUGACAGGAUAGAGAGCUGUGUACUUGAAAUUGAAGGUCUAGCAAGUAGAGCUUUAGUGAAUCUUGGGGUAGGUGCUGUCUCUCUGGGUUAGUAUAUUAGAAUGGGAGUGGGGAACCUUUUUUAUAUAGAGGACCUCUGGCCUACAGAGAGAAAUCAAUCAGUAGCUACUUAAAAAUAGCAGAAGUGGGGUUUGGGAAAAGCAAAAAACAAAAUGUUCUGUAUGAUCCCUGUGUUACAUUAAAAACAUAAUUUUAAUGUUUUUAAUCUACAAAUGAUAGAGUGCAAAUAAUGAGAAAUACAUUUAAAAGGCAUGUUGUACUUAAGUUUCAUCACUAAGUAAAUUGAGAAGGUGGGAAAAAAUAGCAGAGGAAUGGAAGAAAGAGCUAAUAGAGGAAGAGCAACAGUGAGAUAGAUACCAAGAAGACUCAGAAAGGCAUACACAGGGCUGGAGAGAGACACACAAAAUCUCCUACAUAAAAGAGAGCUAUAGAGAGGGAAGCCUGCUGCUUCCAGAGGAACAGCCUAUCCAGGAAACUUUUUAGGUACUGUCAUGAAAACUGUUAAAAACCAUGCCCUAUUUAUAGUUCUAGACAUGUAGAUUAUUAUACUCUUUGUGGGCUGAAUUUCUUUAAACCCCACGAGCUGAGGGCUUCUACCUGUAAUUUAGAAAAAUAAGAGUUUAGGUACCCUAAAUCCACUCAGGUUAUCGUUUUGAAAUUCCUUGAAUGAUAGGAUUUUACAGCAGCAAUAGUAUUAAGUCUUAUGAGUCUUGUUUUUCAUUUAGUAAGUAUUUAUUAAGUGCCUUCUAUGUGUGGGUACAGUUCAGCCUUUGAGAUACAUUCCUGCCUUUGUGGAGCCUACAUUGUAGUAGGAAGAAACCAAAUUGAAAGUAUUUUCGCAGGAAUAUGUGUAUGUUUGUGUGUCUUCUACAUGAGACAUUUCAGCGGCAGCCCAGAAAACUCAAUCCACAUUAAGAAUAUAGUCGUCUCUCUUUUGAACUCUUCUAUUAAGAAUGCUGUUAGCUAAUUACAGAAAACAUAAUGGGCCAAUACCUUUAUUAUAUGAAGAUCCAUUCAAACUAAUUUUAAAAAAAGAUCUAGUAGAUUAAUAGAGACAUGAACAGGAAAUUCAUGCAAGAAGAACUAAUAUAUGCACAUGGAAAAUGUUCUAUUUUCCUAUUAGUCAAGGAAAUGCAAAUUAUGACAAUAAUAUUGAGCCGUUUUCCAUCUCCUGUUUUAUGUAUGUAUAUAUGUGUAUUUGUUUUUAUUAAAUAAUACCAGCUAUUGCCCGGGCAUGGUGGUUCACACCUGUAACCCUAGCACUUUGGGAGGCCAAGGCGAGAGAAUGCCUUGAGGGAAGGAGUUUGAGGCCAGGAUUUCAAGACUAGCCUGGGCAACAUGGUGAGACCCUGUCUCUACGAAAAUAUUUGAAAAUUAGCCAGGUGUGGUGGUUCAUGCCUGUGGGAGGCUGAGGUAGGAGGAUCUCUUGAGCCCAGGAGUUGGAGGUUACAGUGAGCUAUGAUUGCACCACUGCACUCCAGCCUGGAUGACAGAGCAGGACCCUGUCUCAAAGAAUAAUAAUAACAAUGAUAAUAAUACCAGGUAUUGUUGCCAAACUGAUAGCUCAUGUAUUGGUGUUGACAAUAUAAACUGGUGAGUAAUUUUAGGAAGUAAAUCAAUGAUAUGAAUCACACCAUAAAAAUAUUCAUACUCUUAAAAAUAAUCCCAUUUUUGAGAAUAUUUCCAAAAAGAAGGCUAUAUGUUUAAAGGUAUUCAUUGUAGCAUAGUCUUCAUAAUUACUUUAGAACACUUAAGACUUUUACCAUGUUAAAUAACCCUGUAGUUUAAAAUAUAGGCUUAUGGGGGAAAAAAUAGCAAUUUUCAAAAUUAUAUUUACUCUGAAUGUAACUGUAUAAAAAUAUGUGUAUGGACAAAGACUGGAAAGAAAAAAAUAGAUGUGGUUAAGUAGUAGAAUUCUAGUAGAUAUUUUUCUCUUAAGUCUGCCUUCUAGAUGGGAAAUUACAUUAUGAGUAAUUAGCCAAAAACAGGUUUAAGUUCUCAAGGAGUUAAAGUUUUUGUUUCAGCAGGCUAAUAAAAAUACUGUCUGGUGCUGUAUAUUGACACAGUUCUUCUGCUAACUUUUGUCUGUGUAUUUUUCAGUCAAUAAGCAGAUAAAUGACAAAGAGCGAGUGGCAGCUGCAAUGGAAAACCCCAACUUACGGGAAAUUGUGGAACAGUGUGUCCUUGAACCUGACUGAUAGCUGUUUUAAGAGCCACUGGCCUGUAAUUGUUUGAUAUAUUUGUUUAAACUCUUUGUAUAAUGUCAGAGACUCAUGUUUAAUACAUAGGUGAUUUGUACCUCAGAGUAUUUUUUAAAGGAUUCUUUCCAAGCGAGAUUUAAUUAUAAGGUAGUACCUAAUUUGUUCAAUGUAUAACAUUCUCAGGAUUUGUAACACUUAAAUGAUCAGACAGAAUAAUAUUUUCUAGUUAUUAUGUGCAAGAUGAGUUGCUAUUUUUCUGAUGCUCAUUCUGAUACAACUAUUUUUCGUGUCAAAUAUCUACUGUGCCCAAAUGUACUCAAUUUAAAUCAUUACUCUGUAAAAUAAAUAAGCAGAUGAUUCUUA